CCUUCUACAACUUGGUGUCUGAGAGGUUUUGUCUCCGGCUGGUCAUGCUACAUUUCUUGGUUCCCUGACCGGGAAACGAGGCAGACAAAACCUGGGUAGUUAAGGGGCUACCCGAGGCAGCCCCUUAGGCGGCUUAGGCCUGCUGUGUGGAGCAUCCCUGCAGGGGACUCCAGCCAGCCUGAGUGAAGCCAUCCGAAGAGCGAUCCCAGGUAGAGAAUUGCCCCGGUGGAACGCCUCGCCAGAGCAGUGCGUAGCAGGCCCCUGCGGAGGAUUAACACAGUGGCUGAACACCAGGAAGGAACUGGCACUUGGAGUCCAGACAUCUGAAAUUUAACGGAGUAGUCAAGGAAGGCCUCGCUGUGCAGACAACACUGAGCAAAGACUUGAAGGAAGAAAGGGAACAAGAUAUCAAGAUAUUUGGGAAAAGCAUAUUCCAGGCAGAGGUCUGAGCAAAUGCAAAGACCUGACCUGAAGGGAGAAUAUCUCUGGGUGUUCAAGGAACAGUAAGGAGGCCAGAUGGUUGAAACCAGCUGAGAAAAAGGUGCAGUAACUUUAAAUUCCUCAAAUCCCCUGAGUGCAAGGCCAUGGCUCAGAAAAGCCUUGCAAACAACAGCAUUAAUCUCCCCUACAAGGACUUGACCUCCGAGGUAACCAGGCGCCGAGUCACCAUGAUCACAAGAAAAGAGAUAAUUACCCAGAAAAGUGAUGAAGCUAAGGAGAUGCUCUCCCACUUGGAUUUGGAGCAAGCCCCUCCCCCUCACAGGACCUACCUCACAGUACCUCCUGCCCCACCUCCUUCUCCAGCUGAGGAUCCCACGGUCUCCUAAGAUGUAAAACUUAUUUUGAAGUGAAUUCUUACACAGAACUCCAGAAAACAGUUUCAGUGGCAUUCUUGAGGUUUGUCUUAGAAGACUCUUGAAGAUCUUUGUUCUUUCCUAUUUUUCUUCACCUAGAACCACCAUAGAGCAUGGUUUACCCUUGCUAAUAGACUUAGUCAUUUUUGGUUUUUUAAUCCAAGUCUCUGAUAUGAUAUGCAUAUAUUUUGAUCUUUAUGUUAUGCUAUAGAACUGUUGCUGUAGUCAGUUGUAUUUAAAUUAAUAAACAGUUAUCAGGC